AGUCUAGUUAGUAUCGGCCUGUUAUCUCCUUUUGCGCGACACGGUCUCAGCUGUUCCGCCUGAGGCGAGUGACGCUGGCCGCCAACGAGGUAUACGUACUGGGACCCUCGCCCUCAGUCUCGUCUCCGGCGCGGCUACCUGCCCCGUUUUCCCUGUGAGUUGACCUGCUCCGGGCCGCGGGCCGCCAAUGGCAGGGGCCGCUCCGACCACGGCCUUCGGGCAGGCGGUGAUCGGCCCGCCGGGCUCAGGGAAGACCACGUACUGCCUGGGCAUGAGUGAGUUCCUGCGCGCGCUGGGCCGGCGCGUGGCGGUGGUGAACCUGGACCCGGCCAACGAGGGGCUGCCGUACGAGUGUGCCGUGGACGUGGGCGAGCUGGUGGGGCUGGGCGACGUGAUGGACGCGCUGCGCCUGGGGCCCAACGGCGGCCUGCUCUACUGCAUGGAGUACCUGGAAGCCAACCUGGACUGGCUGCGUGCCAAGCUCGACCCCCUCCGCGGCCACUACUUCCUCUUCGACUGCCCAGGCCAGGUGGAGCUCUGCACGCAUCACGGCGCCUUGCGCAGCAUCUUCUCCCAAAUGGCGCAGUGGGACCUCAGGCUGACUGCCGUCCACCUCGUGGAUUCUCACUACUGCACAGACCCUGCCAAGUUCAUUUCAGUACUGUGUACCUCCCUGGCCACCAUGCUGCACGUGGAACUGCCCCACAUCAACCUCCUUUCCAAGAUGGACCUCAUUGAGCAUUAUGGGAAGCUGGCCUUCAACCUGGACUACUACACAGAGGUUCUGGACCUCUCCUACCUGCUUGACCACCUGGCUUCUGACCCUUUCUUCCGCCACUACCGCCAGCUCAAUGAGAAGCUAGUGCAGCUCAUCGAAGACUAUAGCCUUGUCUCCUUUAUCCCUCUCAACAUCCAGGACAAGGAGAGCAUCCAGCGAGUCCUGCAGGCUGUGGAUAAAGCCAAUGGAUACUGUUUCAGAGCCCAAGAGCAGCGAAGCUUGGAAGCCAUGAUGUCUGCCGCAAUGGGAGCCGACUUCCAUUUCUCUUCCACACUGGGCAUCCAGGAGAAGUACCUGGCACCCUCGAACCAGUCAGUGGAGCAGGAAGCCAUGCAGCUGUAGCAACAAGGUGGACCCUGGAGAGCAGGAUGCAUAAUCCAGCACUGGGGAAAGUGGAGGCUCCUGAUGCAGGCUGCAGACCCAAGAGCAAGUCCUCCCAGCCAGAGCUGGCGGGCUGGCAAGGGGAUAUUCAGCUCUGCAAAGGACUUCUGGCCAAAAAGCCAGACAUGGUGCCAAGCAGAACACCCCCCAUACUGUCAGUGGUGUCCGUGAGCUCUGGGCCCUGCCACCAGAAAGUCGAGCACUGGUCCUAGUCAGGCUGUGAUGAAAUGUGCUACAAUACAAGAGUUUAUUUUCUACUUUUUGUGACUUCCAAACUUUUCUUCAGUCUUCCGGGCCCAGGGGUUUGGGGAAGAAUGAGGGAGUGUCACCUAGCCUUGGAAUAAUCAGUAUUUCCCCAAAGCAUAUAAUUCACAUUCAGUCACAUAGGAUUUACAUUCAGUCUCCAGUCAUGUGUUUUUAUUAAUCUUCAGUUUUUGGUUCUGAGGUUUGUUUUUUAAAAGAUGGGGUCUUGCUAUAUGGCCCAGGCUGGACUCAAACUCCUGGGCUCAUGUGAUCUUCCCGCCUCAGACGCCUGAGUAACUGGGACUACAGGUGUGAGCCACCAUGUCCCACAAUUUUCAGUUUUAACAGAGCCUCAAGCUUCAGCUUUCACAGGCAACACUUCCUAACUAGAACUUUGUUAAUGUUUUAUAUUCACUGUAUUUGUUUUAUGGUUUUAUUCUAUUGUUGACAAGUGUUAACUAGUUUUCCAUUUACAGUAGUGGUUAAAAGUUUACUUCAAGGCUGGGUGCGGUGGCUCACGCCUGUAAUCCCAGCACUUUGGGAGGCCGAGGCAGGCGGAUCCCAAGGUCAAGAGAUCGAGACCAUCCUGGCCAACAUGGUGAAACCCCAUCUCUACCAAAAAAUUUUUUUAAUUAGCUGGGCAUAGGUGGCGCGUACCUGUAGUUCCAGCUACUUGGGAGGCUGAGGCAGGAGAAUCAUUUGAACCCAGGAGUCAGAGGUUACAGUGAGCUGAGAUUGCACCACUGCACUCCAGCCUGGUGACAGAGCGAGACUUUGUCUCAAAAAAAAGGUGUACUUCAAAAAUGAAAUACAAGGCUGGGCGUGUUCACUCAUGCCUGUAAGCCCAGCACUUUGGGAGGCUGAGGCGGGCGGAUCACCUGAGGUCAGGAGUUCGAGACCAGCCUGGCCAACAUGGUGAAACCCCUCUCUACUAAAAACAUAAAAAUUAGCUGGGCAUGGUGUUGCACGCCUAUAAUCCCAGCUAUUGGGGAGGCUGAGGCAGAAGAAUUGCUUGAACCCAGGAGGCGGAGGUUGCAGUGAGCCAAGAUUGUGCCUACAUUCCAACCUGGGCGACAGAGCAAGACUCUGUCUCAAAAAAAAAUAGUAAGUUGUGUAAAGAAAAAUAUUAAUUAUAUAAUAUGGCAGUUCCUAUGAGAGUGUGGCAAAAAUCAAGAGGGCUUGGAAGUUUUUUCUUUGCUCUUGCAACUGGCUGGAUGCAGUUCAUAUAUUUUUCAACCAGUAGGUGGCACCCCAACCUAAUUUUUUGCAGUUGUAACCUGGUGGCAGAAGGGGCAGGACUGAUGGCUUGGGCAAGACUGUUAUGCCAAGUUUUAUUUGCAUGUAUUUGGACUUUCUUUUUUUGGAGACAAAGUCUCUCUCUGUCGCCCAGGCUGGAGUCCAGUGGCACAAUCUCGGCUCACUGCAACCUCCGCCUCCCAGGUUCAAGCAAUUCUCUGCCUCAGCCUCCCGAGUAGCUGGGAUUACAGGCGCCUACCACAUGCCCGGCUAAUUUUUGUAUUUUUAGUAAAGACGGGGUUUCACCAUGUUGUUCAGGCUGGUCUUGAACUACUGACCUCAUGAUUUACCCGCCUUGGCCUCCCAAAGUGCUGGGAUUACAGGCGUGAGCCACUGCACCCGGCCACAUUUGGACUUAUUAACACAUAUGAAGUGCUUGGUAUUUUAGAGUGCUUCCACACACACAAUCCUCAUUAGAGAUAGACAGGAUGGGGAGAAUUAAUAAGCCAUUGCCCGUGUUACAGUGAGGAAGCAGAAAGAUGAGAAGUUUGAACUUUGGUCAGCCUGGCUUUCUCAUAACCCAUUUUGCUGACUAAAUUGCGAGUAUCCCUCCUUUGGUAUAUUUAUUGGUGAGAAGUCACAGCCCUUGUCCCACAGGUUUUGCAGCCAAUCAGGAGAAAGAAAUUAGGCACCUGUAAAGUAUUACUGAAUCAUAGAUAGUUCACCAGUGGUUUGGGCAGUUGGCAAAUUAAUUUAGGGACAUCUGUUCUGAAACAGCAUUGAAAUAGGACUGACUGCUUUGCUUUCUGGUUGUGGCAGCCAGAGCCAAAGGCAGAUGAAUGAGGGGCUAUGAGGAGGCUACUGUGGCUGGAACAGUAUGAAAGCAACCUCAGCUCCCACGCCUGGCUGUAAAGGGGAUAAUAACUGGGUGCUGCUUCCCAGCCUCUUUCAUCUGAGAAGUUCAAAGCACCUCACCCCUAUUAACACCCCACAGAGUAGGUAGGAAGUACCAAUAGAGCAAGCCAGGAAAACUGAGGCCAGGAGGCACAGCCUGGGGCUAGCUGUGAAUCACCUGUGGGGCCUAGAGCCCAGGAAUCCUGACGCCCAGGCUACUGGACAAAUCCUUUAUCAGGGCAUUAGGGUGGGUGCUAUGCUUUUGAAAGCAGUACCAACGGCUGUGGUCGUGGGUUUUGAUGCUUGCCACUCACAGAGGCCCCAGCUCUCACCAUAACAAACCAAAUGGGGGCUGGAAGGCAUCCUUUACAACUUUAUGGUCUCGUAUGCAAGCACCCUCAGCAUUCUCUGCACCCAUGGAGUGGAGAUGGGUGGGAGUAAUCCAAGGCCUUUAUUUUCAGGCCAUGGUUUGACAGCAAGGGUAUUUUCUUCCCCAAUAAACGUAGCUUCUGUCUACCUUCCACUGGCAGCAAAAUGAUUUUCUGUUCUCUGCAUAUACUGAGGGGAUCUGCACAGUGCAGAAAGGAAGAUGUCCGAGAUCCAAGUGAGGCCUGUUCAGUGUGAAAUGUCUAGGGUAGAAGAAAGACCAUCCUCCAUUAUGGCUGGCAUGUGGCAGUCAUCCUUAAGAUUAUUUUUAAAUUUCCUAAUAAAUAUAGGAAAGUAAAAAACUUAGAAAAUGAAAGAGAAGGCCGAGCACGGUGGCUCACGCCUGUAAUCCCAGCACUUUGGGAGGCCAAGGCGGGCUGAUCACCUGAGGUCAGGAGUGUAAGACAAGCCUGACCAACAUGGUGAAAACCUGUCUCUGCUAAAAAUACAAAAAAAUGAGCAGGGCAUGGUGGCAUGCGCCUGUAAUUCCAGCUACUUAGGAGACUGAGGCAGGAGAAUCGCUUGAACCUGGGAGGCGGAAGUUUCAGUGAGCGGAGAUCGCGCCAUUGCACUCCAGCCUGGGUAACAAGAUGGAAAGUACAUCUCAAAAAAAAAAAAAACGAAAAUGAGUCACCCAGAAUCCCAUAACGGAAACUUUCUAUGGGGUCAUCUGUUUAAGAGAAAAAUAAAUUCUAUAUUCAAAUGUA